UUAGCGUAAUGUCUGGGAAAUUCAUUGCAUAUAUCGGAAAUGCAUUGCAUGUGUAAUGCAUAUGUCAGAAAUGCGUUGUUCUUUACUGACAAAUAUAUUCUGUUGUAUGGACAGACCACAGUUUCUUUGUUUUACUGCAGAUGGACACUUGGGUUGUUUCCAAUUUUUGACAAAUUGAGUGAUGUAUGAAUAUUCAUGCACACAUCUUUGUACGGACAUGGGGUUCUGUUUCUCUUGAGUAAAUCCUGAAGAAUGCAGUUGCCAGGUCACAUGUUUGUAAGAAGCUAUCAAAUUGUUUUCCACAGUGGUUGUACCAUGUUUUACUCACAUCACCAAUGUAUGAGAGUUUCAGUUACUCCACAUCCUCAGCAGCACUUGGAAUUGUCAGUGCGGUGAGGUGGAAUCUCACUGGGGUUUAAGUUAUAAUUGCCUGAUAACUAAUGAUGCUGAGCAUCUUUCCAUCCAUGUAUCUUCUUUGAUGACAUAUCUGUUCAAAUCUUUUAAGGGUAUUUGUUUUUAACAUUGAAAAUAUAUGGCAUUUUGAUCCUAAAAAUGACAGAAAUUCCUUAAUACAUGGUCAGAUUUAUUUGGUGUCUACAUAAGGUUUAAUAGUGGAAGAAUAGAGAGAUCUCCACAACAAAUGCAAGACUGAGAUUAAAUGUCUUUCGAAGUUUUGGAAGCAACUACUUAAACAGCAGGAUAUUUAGAGAAAAAUGUUAGACAUGUUUAUACCCCCACACCCCACUUUUUUUUUUAAUGAGCCUUGAGAGAAGGAUGAAAUAUUUCUAAAUAGCUAUAGCAAAGCAGCUGUUUUGAAAUGCCUGGUGGUGAAAGUCCCUCUUAACUGCACUCUGUCCUGGAGGCACAAGGUUGAGCAUUUCUGCUUCUCCCGGCUGCUUCACUGUCACCAGACAGCCCAUUUUUUCUUAUGAUAAAGACGGCAUUUGGCUCAUGAGCAAGGUGGCAAGAUCAUCAAGUGAGUCAGACGUGCAGCUCUGGGAAACAGAAGAGGAUGACAUGACAGAAGGUGAUUUAGGGUAUGGCCUCGGAAGGAAACCUGGUGGGAUUUAUGAAAUAGAAUUUUCACAUAGGUCUAGAAAAAGAUCAGAUGGAAAGAACUUUAGCCCUCCUCCAUUUCCGAGAAAGGGAGAAGAAAGAAAUGAAGCGAGUUUUCAGUAUUCCAAGCAUAAGAGCCAGCAAGAUACAUUCCCUCAAGUGUCCAGAAUUUCCAAUUACAGACGACAAAGUAGCACUGUAGAUUCGAAUUCAGAAUUGUCAAAUGAAGAAUUAAGGCAAUGUCUUAAUGAAACUUUAGAGGAGGUAGAAAUGUUAAAAACUGAACUUGAGGCAUCUCAAAGACAACUCAGAGGUAAAGAGGAAGCAUUGAAAAUUCUUCAAAGCAUGGCAAUACUGGGCAAAGCCACAAGUCAUACGCAGGCAGUGCUUCAAAAAACUAUGGAACAAAACAGAUCCUUGGAGAAGGAAAUAAAUGCCUUGCAGUGGGAAAUAGAAUUUGAUCAUAAUAGAUUUAAAAAUAUAGAGGAAUCUUGGAUCCAAAAAUAUGACAGGCUAAACUGUGAAAAUGCAGUCCUCAAAGAGAAUUUGAAAGUGAAAACAGAAGAAAUUAAAAUGCUGAAGUCUGACAAUGCAGUUUUGAAUCAACGGUAUUUGGAGGCCCUCGCCAUGCUUGAUAUCAAACAGCAGAAGAUGGCUCAGGAAAACAUGUGCUGUGAUAAAAGUGGCUUUGCAGAGGCUUCAGGUCUUGAGCUUGCGGUCCUCGGAGCCUGCCUUUGUCAUGGGCCCGGAGGGAACCCCUGUUCUUGUGCCAGAAUGGCAGCAUCCACUCGGAAACUGCUUCUUCAGCUCAAACAAGAGUUGGAAAUUUUGCAGAAGAGUAAAGAAGAAGCUUACGUGAUGGCAGAUGCUUUCAGAAUUGCAUUUGAGCAACAAUUAAUGAGAAAAAAUGACCAGGCACUACAAUUGACACAAAUGGAUAAAAUGCAUAAAAAAGCAACAAAAUGGAUGAAUUGGAAGCACCUUAAAGAGGAUGGAUUUCCAUCACCAAGGAGUAAGAAGACCUUCGGGCAGAGACUGUUGGGUAUGCUCCCUUCAGAAAACAGUUCUAAGAGGAUGGAAGACCAGGACAGUCCUCAAGAGGUCCUUAAGAUGCUCAUAGAUUUGCUUAAUGAUAAAGAAGAAGCUUUGGCUCAUCAAAGAAAAGUUAGCUACAUGCUUGCUCGGGCAUUGGAAGACAAAGACACUGCUUCAAACGAGAAUAAAGAAAAAAAUCCUAUAAAAGAGAAUUUCCCUUUCAACAACCCCUGGCGUAAGACUUCAGAAUUCUCUGUUUUGGGUGAUCCUAUACAUUCAAGUGUCUGCAUUUUAAAUUCUGUGGGCUGCAUUUGUUCAAUCCAGCACUCUCAAAUAGAUCCAAACUAUAGAACUCUUAAAAGAUCCCAUUCUUUGCCAUCAAGUAUCAUAUUUUAAAGACAAGCCAGUUGAAAUUGGAACUGAGAGUUGUUUAUAUCGAGAUACUUUGAAAAAUGAUUUUGUAAAUUUUGCUGCAUCUUGAGAAGUUGUAUGUUUCCUAGGUAUUUCUAAAUUUUAGGAGGUCGCUUAAAUCAAAUAUUUUCUACAUUUUCUUUUUCUUCUUUUGAGAUGGAGUCUUGCUCUGUCACCCAGGUUGGAGUGCAGUGGUGUGAUCUCGGUUCACUGCAACCUCCGCCUCCCGGUUCAAGCAAUUCUCCUGCCUCAGCCUCCCGAGUAACUCGGAUUACAGGCAUGUGCCACCACGCCCAGCUAAUUUUUGUAUUUUUAGUAGAGACGGGGUUUUACCAUGUUAGCCAGGCUGAUCUUGAACUCCUGACCUCAAGUGAUCCGCCUGCCUUGGCCUCCGAAAGUGCUGGGAUUACAGGCGUGAGCCACCACACCCAGCCUAUUUUCUACAUUUUCUACAAGAAAUUAGUAUUCUGUGUUGACAUUUUAUUUAUAAAUUACAUUACUGUAUUUAUAAAUUACAUUACAGGCUGGGCAUGGUGGCUCAUGCUUAUAAAUCCCAGCACUUUGGGAGGCCAAGGUGGGUGGGUCACCUGAGGCUGGAGUUCAAGACCAGUCUGACCAACAUGGAGAAACCCCAUCUCUACUAAAAAUACAAAAAAUUAGCUAGGCCUAGUGGCGCAUGCCUGUAAUCCCAGCUACUUGGGAGGCUGAGGUAGGAGAAUCGCUUGAACCUGGGAGGCAGGGGUUGUGGUAAGCCGAGACUGUGUCAUUGCACUCCAGCCUGGGCGACAAGAGCGAAACUCUGUCUCAAAAAAAAAAACAAAACACAUUACAGUGUUUGCCAACAUCCUAAAACAAAAAAUAAUGAUUUUUGGGAAAAACAAAAAAUUAUUUAACUAUUUUGAUUGACUAUAGGGAUCUUAGCUUGGCUAAAUCAACAAUAUAGCAAUGUAUCUUAAUGCUCUAAAAAGUAACAAUACCUAGGACUGACUGAAUGUUAAUUUCUGGAAUUCAUUUAUCUUGUUUUAUUUGCCUUGUUCAGUAUUUUUCAUUUACCAUAUGAAGUUUAGAAAUAACAAUUUCCUUAAGUUAACUUCAAUAAGACAGUUUUGAUGGUGGGACCUUGGCAGAAGUAUAUUGAGUCAGUGCCGGCUGCGUUCAUGGCUUCUUGUCAGGGUAGUAACAUUUUGCAACCAAAUCUGCACAGAUUUGUAGCCAAGUCUACAAAGUGCUUAACAGCUCUUUUCAUUGCAUCCUGUGAGAUGGUUGUGAUGAUCCAGGAAAUGGGGUCUCAGGAAUCUGAAGAAGCUGCCUGAGCCAAGGUGAUUUCUAGGAGUUUUUUUGUUUGUGGUAUGUGAAUUGGGGUGUGUGGGGGUGGGGUGUGUGUGUAGACAGGGUCCCACUGUGUUGCUCAGGCUGGUGCCAAACUCCUGGCCUCAAGGGAUCCUCCUGCCUCAGCCUCUCAAAGUGCUGGGAUUACAGGCAUAAACCACAACUCAAUAAAAAAGUUUUUAAAAAUUUACAAAGCUCAUAUUUGAUCCAGCUAGGAUUUUACCCUGUACAUUUGUAUUUCUUGUAGGCUGGCGCACAGAUAUCUUAAAUGGCUACUAAUUGCUGCUGUGUAUGAAAACAAAUGGCUAUCAAGGCCGGGUGCAGUGGCUUACAGAUCUGGUCUGAAUCUCAAGUCCAGACCAGUCCAGAGUUCAAGACCAGCCUGGGCAACAUGGUGAAACCCCAUCUAUACAAAAACUCGGCAAGGCAUGGUGGCAUGCACCUGUUGUCCCAGCUACUCAGGGGCUGAGGCAGGAGGAUGGCAUGAGCCCAGGAGCUUGAGGCUGCAGUGAGCUGUGAUUGUGCCACUGCACUCCAGCCUGAGUGACAGAGUGAGACCCCCAUCUCCAAAAGAAAAGGCUAUCAAUACAAAAGUUUAUCUAAAUUACUGUACAGCUAUACAAUGGAAUACUCUACAAAAUGGAGAGAUCCAUAAGAUAAAGCAAAUGAAUAAAGCAAAAUGCAUGUGUUGACAGCUGUUGUGAUACCUCAGUUCUUGUCUUCUUGGUUUAAAAGAAUUUAAAUGAGACAGCAAAGGAGAUGCAGCAUAAUUUAUUGCAAAAGAAAAGGAGUAUUUUGAAAGUUAGGUGCAGAACAGACAGUACACCUGAGAGAGAGAAUUCAGGGCCGGCUGCUCGUAAGGGUGAGACAGCAUUGAUUAUUGCUGGAGAAACUCCCUUUAUGGGAGUUUUGCAUUAUUAUUCAUAAGGAGGUGAGGUGUUGCAGUAAUCAUGUCCUGGGUGGUCCUCUGCACAGGUGCAGUAGCUGUUAAUGCUUGUUCAUACACCACAUGUCUCAGUAGCAUCUUAAAUUUCCACCUAGAGGUGUGUUUUUUAUUAUUAUCAUGUGCAAAGGAUCAGUUUGAGGACAGGUAAAAUCAAAAUGUGUAUGCUCUCUAGAAGGGAAAGUCCCUACUGAAGAUAGCUUUGCUUAAAUGAGCUCAAUUACAAUGUGAAUGCUGAGGUUUAUUGUGUUGGCUGUAUGGUCAUGAG